AUUCCACAUCAGGAGCGUUUUUGGAGAAAGCUGCACUCUGUUGAGCUCCAGGGCGCAGUGGAGGGAGGGAGUGAAGGAGCUCUCUGUACCCAAGGAAAGUGCAGCUGAGACUCAGACAAGAUUACAAUGAACCAACUCAGCUUCCUGCUGUUUCUCAUAGCGACCACCAGAGGAUGGAGUACAGAUGAGGCUAAUACUUACUUCAAGGAAUGGACCUGUUCUUCGUCUCCAUCUCUGCCCAGAAGCUGCAAGGAAAUCAAAGACGAAUGUCCUAGUGCAUUUGAUGGCCUGUAUUUUCUCCGCACUGAGAAUGGUGUUAUCUACCAGACCUUCUGUGACAUGACCUCUGGGGGUGGCGGCUGGACCCUGGUGGCCAGCGUGCACGAGAAUGACAUGCGUGGGAAGUGCACGGUGGGCGAUCGCUGGUCCAGUCAGCAGGGCAGCAAAGCAGUCUACCCAGAGGGGGACGGCAACUGGGCCAACUACAACACCUUUGGAUCUGCAGAGGCGGCCACGAGCGAUGACUACAAGAACCCUGGCUACUACGACAUCCAGGCCAAGGACCUGGGCAUCUGGCACGUGCCCAAUAAGUCCCCCAUGCAGCACUGGAGAAACAGCUCCCUGCUGAGGUACCGCACGGACACUGGCUUCCUCCAGACACUGGGACAUAAUCUGUUUGGCAUCUACCAGAAAUAUCCAGUGAAAUAUGGAGAAGGAAAGUGUUGGACUGACAACGGCCCGGUGAUCCCUGUGGUCUAUGAUUUUGGCGACGCCCAGAAAACAGCAUCUUAUUACUCACCCUAUGGCCAGCGGGAAUUCACUGCGGGAUUUGUUCAGUUCAGGGUAUUUAAUAACGAGAGAGCAGCCAACGCCUUGUGUGCUGGAAUGAGGGUCACCGGAUGUAACACUGAGCACCACUGCAUUGGUGGAGGAGGAUACUUUCCAGAGGCCAGUCCCCAGCAGUGUGGAGAUUUUUCUGGUUUUGAUUGGAGUGGAUAUGGAACUCAUGUUGGUUACAGCAGCAGCCGUGAGAUAACUGAGGCAGCUGUGCUUCUAUUCUAUCGUUGAGAGUUUUGUGGGAGGGAACCCAGACCUCUCCUCCCAACCAUGAGAUCCCAAGGAUGGAGAACAACUUACCCAGUAGCUAGAAUGUUAAUGGCAGAAGAGAAAACAAUAAAUCAUAUUGACUCAA